CGGCGCCGGCCCUAGGUCCCGGCAGCGGUGGUGACGGCGGUGCCGGAGGUUGUCCUUGGCAGGUUUUCCUCGGCGCUUCUCCAUGGAGGAGGCGGUGCGAACGGCUUCAGCCCCGAAUGCUCGCAUCUCCCACUGGACGGCGACGAAGGCGGUGGCCGUGCGAGCGCAGGACUGGGCGGCCUGUGUGGGGGUGUGAGCCGCGGUGCCCAAGGCUGCGCCGGCGAGGGGAAGCCGCGCGGCCGGCCGGCCGACUAGGGUGAGGUCGCCACUCCUUCCUUUCAGGCAAGCGCGAAGGGGCUGACUUGGUGGCGAGCCAGCCCGCCUUGUGUCGGAGAAGGGUUCUUCGGGCAACUUUCCUUUCCGGGUGUUCUGAAGCGGUUUUCCUGUAAUCCUCAGUGAGGAAACCCACCGUGAAUCGGAUUGCCGUUCAGUCCCACGGAAGCCUGGCUCGUUGGCCAUGUCGGGGACGCAUGUUCAUUAAGUUCAUUAAAAUAAUUUCAUUUGUCUUGGCUGGAGCUACUCGGCCAGGGUUUAAGACUUUAAAUGAGAAUAAAGGGUGGUAUUUACGAGGAAAUGAGAGUGAAUAAGUCAUCUCUAACCUCUCCCAGCCUUUUUUUCAUAAGAGAGACCAUAUUAAACUUACAUGGGUCGUGAUUCCAAAUUCUUCAGCAGAAGGCUGAGAUUGGCAGAGAUGAGGAGGCCUGGAUUAUAGUUCUGCUUCUGCUACCUCAGCUGUGUGACGUGUUACUUAACAUCUCUGGACUUGGGCCAGGUGCGGUGGCUCACGCCUGUAAUCCCAGCACUUUAGGAGGCCAAGGCUGUUGGAUCACGAGGCUCUCCCGGCUGUGAUAGACCUUCAGUUACAGAGAGAGGGAGCAGAGUGGGACCAGGUCUGAGAAUAGUGAAGCAACUCAUUCCUUUCAGGACAUUCCCUCUGAUGUCCUAUUUUCAAACUUUCAUCUGUCAACUGAGUUUAUGAGUUGGCCAUUUGGAAAAACAAUUGCAGUCUUGGUAAGCCUCUGCUUCCUGUCUGGCCUCGAGGAUUGAGCCCUCCAGAUACCAUGGUCCUCAUGUUCUCCAAAGGCCACCGGUACCAUACUGCACGCCCCAGCAGACACCUCUCUGCAAGAAUUGUUACCCUCUGAUAAAUAAUGUGAAAUCUGCCUUCUCUCAGCACAUCCCUGAAUAGGCUAAAUAAAUAAAUUAGCAUAUGCUUAUGUGCACCUAUUGCUAAGAAGAAAAUGUAUGGGUUUGAAGACUGCUUCAUUCUGCCUCUAGUACCAGCGGUUUCUCUGUUCUGUGAUCAAUGUGAUUCACAGGAACUCCUUAAGUAACAAACGAAAUGAGCCAGGGGCGUGGAAAAUAUGACUUCUAUAUUGGUCUGGGAUUGGCUAUGAGCUCCAGCAUUUUCAUUGGAGGAAGUUUCAUUUUGAAAAAAAAGGGCCUCCUUCGACUUGCCAGGAAAGGCUCUAUGAGAGCAGGUCAAGGUGGCCAUGCAUAUCUUAAGGAAUGGUUGUGGUGGGCUGGACUGCUGUCAAUGGGAGCUGGUGAGGUGGCCAACUUCGCUGCGUAUGCGUUUGCACCAGCCACUCUAGUGACUCCACUAGGAGCUCUCAGCGUGCUAGUAAGUGCCAUUCUUUCUUCAUACUUUCUCAAUGAAAGACUUAAUCUUCAUGGGAAAAUUGGGUGUUUGCUAAGUAUUCUAGGAUCUACAGUUAUGGUCAUUCAUGCUCCAAAGGAAGAGGAGAUUGAGACUUUAAAUGAAAUGUCUCACAAGCUAGGUGAUCCAGGUUUUGUGGUCUUUGCAACCCUUGUGGUCAUUGUGGCCUUGAUAUUAAUCUUCGUGGUGGGUCCUCGCCAUGGACAGACAAACAUUCUUGUGUACAUAACAAUCUGCUCUGUAAUCGGCGCGUUUUCAGUCUCCUGUGUGAAGGGCCUGGGCAUUGCUAUCAAGGAGCUGUUUGCAGGGAAGCCUGUGCUGCGGCAUCCCCUGGCUUGGAUUCUGCUGCUGAGCCUCAUCGUCUGUGUGAGCACACAGAUUAAUUACCUAAAUAGGGCCCUGGAUAUAUUCAACACUUCCAUUGUGACUCCAAUAUAUUAUGUAUUCUUUACAACAUCAGUUUUAACUUGUUCAGCUAUUCUUUUUAAGGAGUGGCAAGAUAUGCCUGUUGACGAUGUCAUUGGUACUUUGAGUGGCUUCUUUACAAUCAUUGUGGGGAUAUUCUUGUUGCAUGCCUUUAAAGACGUCAGCUUUAGUCUAGCAAGUCUGCCUGUGUCUUUUCGAAAAGACGAGAAAGCAAUGAAUGGCAAUCUCUCUAAUAUGUAUGAAGUUCUUAAUAAUAAUGAAGAAAGCUUAACCUGUGGAAUCGAACAACACACUGGUGAAAAUGUCUCCCGAAGAAAUGGAAAUCUGACAGCUUUUUAAGAAAGGUGUAAUUAAAGGUUAAUCUGUGAUUGUUAUGAAGUGAAUUUGAAUAUCAUCAGAAUGUGUCUGAAAAAACAUUGUCCUCAAAUAAUGUUCUUUAAAGGCAAUCUUUUUAAAGAUUUCACUAAUUUGGACCAAGAAAUUACUUUUCUUGUAUUUAAACAAACAAUGGUAGCUCACUAAAAUGACCUCAGCACAUGACGAUUUCUAUUAACAUUUUAUUGUUGUAGAAGUAUUUUACAUUUUCAUCCCUUCUCCAAAAGCCGAAUGCACUAAUGACAGUUUUAAGUCUAUGAAAAUGCUUUAUUUUUUCAUUGGUGAUGAAAGUCUGAAAUGUGCAUUUGUCAUCCCCACUCCAUCAAUCCCUGACCAUGUAAGGCUUUUUUAUUUUAAAAAAACAGAGUUAUCCCAAUACAUUAUCCUGUGAUUUACCUUACCUACAAAAGUGGCUCCUGUUUGUUUGAUGAUGAUUGGUUUUAUUUUUGAAAUAUUUAUUAAGGGAAAACUAAGUUACUGAAUGAAGGAACCUCUUUCUUACAAAACAAAAAAAAGGGCAGAAAUCACCCCAAGGAACGAUUUCUCAGGUUGAGAUGAUCACCGUGAAUCCGGCUUCCUCUGAGCAUUCGAUGGCCUUAGCACCUCAUCAAGCCAGCACAUCCUGCCUGCUGUUGCAGCCUGGCUGGGUUUAUUCUUCAGUUACCCUAAUCCCAUGAUGCCUGGAACCUUGAUUACCGUUUUACAUCAGCUCUUGUACUUUUCAGUAUAUUUUCAUAAUGAGUUAUAUUGUCAUUUAGACUUUGAACAGCUCUGGGAAAUAGAAGACUAGGGUUGUUUCUUAAAUUUAGCUCAUGUUAUAAUAAAAAGUUGAAAUGAAGUUCUUAUUCUAAAAGUCUGAAUGCUUAGAACAAACUUAACAUGUUUAUAGAAUAUGGUCUCUUUGUACCAAGUACUUUGCUUAAGAGCUCCUUUGGGCCACUACAUAUUUUGGUUUCUAGAAAAUGUUUGUUUAUGAAGAAGUCGAUGGAAAACUGCAAACAUAUGCAGAAAAGGUAGAAUAAUAAAAAAGGUCUAAUGAACUCCAUUCAGCUUUGAACCUAUCCACUCAUAACCAUUGACUGGCCUUUAAAAAAAAGUAUUGGCAGAAUUAAUUUCCACCUAGGUGAUGGGAAGAAAGUGUUCGCCUGUUCCAGCCUGUGGCUCCUGCCUGGAGGUUACCCAGUGGUGCGCCAGCGCCAAGCCAUCACUCCCCGAGGGCCUCCCCUGCCAAUGGUGCUGGUAUCCCAUGCAGCUCACCACUGGCUGCGUGGAAACUCCCUUUUUUCCAACUUUAUUAUUGGCCUUCUAAGGAGCUGUUUUAGAUGUUUUUUCUAACUGCCUCCUCCCAUGCCAUUUUAAUACUACAGAUGUACUACGUAUCUGUUUAUAUACUGUACCUACAUCUGUGCUUUGUACAUAAAAGAACCAGUUUUCUCCCCCUUGAGGACAGAGACUCAUUUGAACAUGCAUAGGUUAAUAAAUAAUAAAUUCUUAUUUAACA